AGUGUAUUUUGAUUCGUGUCCUGGGAGAUCAGGAGGUAAGGUAGUGGGGAGGAAAAACUUUUAGACCUAGCAAGGCUCCCAUUUAUUCAAAAAAUAGCUAGUAAAUUGGAGGCUAGGGAUUCUCACCGUAAGAAUUUUGAGAGUCUGAUUUUUGUGUGGUACCAGGCAUUUAUAAACAUAUGUUGAAUGCUGAAUUGUUGAACAUUUGAACAUCUCCAGAUUUGUUAUUUUUAUUAUCCUGUCUUUGUUACCUUGAAUUGGUUAAUAGCAAAACCUUUAGAAUCAGAGACUCUGUGUGCUUGUUAUGGGGGGCAACAAUGAAAGUCAGGGUGCAGCUAAUGAGAUUGUAUUUUACUUAUAGCCAGGAUUGUGGAAGAAGACACUCAAAGGAUAAGAGGCUUACCAUUUUUCCCAUUCUGUAAAACCAUGUUGAUGACAAUACCAAUUCUGAGAGUUGUUUUGAAAUACUGAGUUAAUAUAUGAAAAGGGUCUGGUACAUGAUAGAUAGUAAUUGAGAUGUUUUUGUUACCAGUAUUAUUAUCUUCACAAGUGGGGGGCAAACACAGAGAUCCCAGAACCUAUUAUAAGAAAAAAAGGAAAACAUCUGGAGACCCUUUGUACUUGAAAAAGGGCUCAGGACUAAGUCAUAGAAGGACUGUAGGUUUCCUUUCUUGGAAGGUUUUCUAGGGUUUGGUACAAUUGGGUAGAGCAUGAUGUUGAAUUAAGUAGUAAAAUAUAUCCAUCUCAACUAUUUUCAGUUUCCUGUCAAGUUCUCAGUAAACCAACAGAAAAAUGUUGUUGAGCAUGAGAAGAAGGUUUACUUUUCUUGUCAUACCAUUUUUGGAAACAUUACUUGGAUCCUACUACUUAGGGGUUUUUCUGUAGCAUUUAUUCACUCAAAUAUUUGUUGAGUACCUUCUUUGUCAGGCACUGUUCUAAAGAGAAAAAUCCUUGCCUGCAUGGAGCUUAUCUGCUAAUGGGAGAAAUAAGGUGCAUUUUCAUAAUAGACGGUAAUUAGAUUUUUCUCGUACUAUGUAUUUGUACCUAUUUAAGCAGAUGGUAAUAAUGAAUACUAUACCAGAUUGUAACUAAUUUUGCAGAGCAUUUGAAGGAAGGGACCAUGUCUUUCUUAUUCGCAUUUGUCUCUCCCUUUUCCCCUUCCUCCCAGUGGAAUGGCUUAGAUGUGUUUAAUGCUCAACAAACGUAGGUACUCAUCAAAUGUUUAUUACAGGGAGAAGGUGUUAAGGCAGAGGCUACAUCUUAAAGAUUAAAGGAGUCAGUUAAAUGUGGCAUGUAUUAAGGACCCAUAUACCCCCUAGAUUGAGGGUGAGAAGAAGAGAAUCCGGCUGGGCACUGUGGCUCAUGUCUGUAAUCCCAGCACUUUGGGAGGCUGAGGUGGGCAGAUCACUUGAGACCAGAGUUCGAGGCCAGCCUGGGCAACAUGGUAAAACCCCAUUUGUACUAAAAUACAGAAAUUAGCCAGAUGUGGUGGCGUGCUCAUGUAAUCCCAGUUACUUGAGAGGCUGAGGCAGGAGAAUUGCUUGUACCUGGGAGGCGGAGGUUGCAGUGAGCCAAGACCGCGGCACUGUACUCCAGCCUGGGUGACAGAGCGUGACUCUGUCUCAAAAAAAUAAAAUAAGAUAAAAAUAAAAAGAGAAUCCCCUGGCUUAUCUAUGAGGUUGGAAUAGGAAUAAAGUUAUAUUGUAGCUGAAAGCAUCAACAUUAUGGGAGUCUGGGUGUCACCCAACAUUCCCACUAAUUAGCUGGGUGAUUUUGCAUAAAUAUCUUAACCUCUCAGUUCAUUUCCUCACCUGUAAAUGAAGUAGUUGGAAUUGUCCAGUUAAAAUCUGUUUUUACGACUUCUUGUAAAAUAUCUCUUGCACUAAUGUUUCACUUCACUAACGUAGAUAAUAUAGAGCCAAGCAUGAGCUUCCAUUGAAUAAGCAUCAAGCUAAAUAUAUACUCUUAGUUAAUAAACUAAUGUUUAAGAAAAGAUGUCUACAAAAUUUGUUGAUGCUAUUUACCGGUAAGAUUACAUUGUAAUUUUUUAAAAUAGAGCAAAAUAUUACCUAAUAUAUAGUUUCCCCCAUUGCCAUUAUGUAAAGGAAAAAUAAGCCAUAGUAUUUUAGACCUUAAUAAUGGAUCAUAAUACUCACUUUCAUACUUUAAUUUAUACAACAGUCACUUGCCUCUGAUAUUGUGCUAGAUGCUAGGUAUUGUAUACAGAAUUAGAAAAUGUAUAGCUCCUAACUUUAAGGAGCUUAAGGAAUAAUGGGAGUGACAGACCAUUUAGUUGUGUUGCAUUUUGGUGGCAUAGAGAAGCAUAUAAUGAGAGUCUGGGAGAAGAGAAAGUGCUCAUGGUUACAGAGAAAAAGACUGGAGGAAUGGCAAGGGACUAAGCUAAAUAUACAGAGACGAGCCAGUUUAUGAAGAACUUUGUGCUAAACCACAGUUUAGUUCUGAGCUGUAUUCUGAAAACUGCUUAAUCUGUUAAGGAAUUUUAUGCAGGCAGUAACAUAAUCAGGCAUUUUUAUAUCUACCUUUAUAUUCCUUUUAAGAGAAGGUGUUCCCUGAGGAAGGUAUUUGUUAUUUCUAGUUGUUUCAACGAUGUAGAUCUUCCUGAGGAAAUCAGUCUUUUUAACUUUGAAAUAAAGUCUGAGGAACAUUGUCAAUUUUGUGGUUAUAGAGUUAAUAAUUAUUAAAUAUUAAUAAUUAUGAAAUAUUCAGACAUUAAAACAUUUAAAUGUUUAUUGCCACAUUAAUGUAAACUGAAAAGAAAACUGAAAUUUUGGGAUGUUUUGCGCUUUGAUGUAAGAGAGCUCUUGGUCAGCUACAAGAAUUUGGCUUAGAAUCAUUUUUAAGGAGUUAGAAAUACGUUGACCUUGAAUUGAUUGAAAGUGAAUGUAGUUCAGGCUCAGUUUCUUUCUUUCUUUUUUUUUUGUUUUUUUAAAGAGACCGUCUUUUUCUGUCACCUGGUAUGGUCUCAAACUCCUGGCCCCAAGCAAUCCUCCCUCCUCAGCUUCCCAAAGUGCUGGGAUUACAGGCGUGAGUCACCACUCCCUGCCCGGGCUCUGUUUCUAAUGAUAGAAAUAUCCAGGUAAACUUUAUAGAGGGAAUGAAUUUCCACCGGGAAAUAAUCCUAGUGAGGAGCUGGUGAUAAAUGAAUAUUUCUGAAUGAAGUCAUGAGGGAGAAACAUCUACUUUAUUUAGAUGUGAAACACCUCAUUAAAUGUUGAAGAAUACUUUAUUUGCAUACUUACUAUGUUUGUCAUUUACUCUUUUGACCCUCAAAGAGGAAGAGCUGCUUAUAAUUUCCACAUUUAUCCAACAUGGAUUAUAAAUGUUAAUUGCUUUUUUUGGAAAAAAAAUUGAGGUAAAAAUUCACGUAAUUAACCAUUUUAAAGCAAUAGUUCAGUGGCAUUUAGUACCUUUGCAGUGUUGUGCAACCAUCACUUCUGUCUAGUUUCAAAACAUUUUUAUCACUUUGAAGUAAAAUCUCAUACCUAUUAAGCAGUCAUUCCCUGAUGCCCCUAGCUCAUGGCAACCACAUCUGUUUUCUGUUUUUAUGGAUUUACUUAUUCUGGAUAUUUUAUAUAAAUUGAAUUUUCAAUAUUUGAGUUUUUAUCCCUGGCUUCUUUCACUUAGCAAAAUGUUUUCAAGGUUUACCCACAUGUAGCAUAUAUCAGUACUUCUUUCCUUUUCAUAGCAGAAGAAUAUUCCUUUCCAUGUCAGAAGAAUAUUCCUUUCCAUGUCUAUAUAUCAGUUUGUUUAUCCAUUUAUCCAUCGAUGGAUAUUUGGGUUGUUUCCACCUUUUAGUUAUUAUGAAUAUGUUGCUGUGAAUAUUUGUGUCCAAGGAUUUAUUUGAGAACCUGUUUUCACUUUUUCGGGUAUAUACCAAGAAUGGAAUGCUGGGUCUUAUGGUAAUUUUGUUUAGCUUUUUGAGGACCUGCCAAACUGCUUUCCACAGUAGCUAAACCAUUUUACAUUCCCACUGGCAAUGUGUGAGGGUUCCAAUUUCCCUACAUCCUUGCCUACACUUAUUUUCUGUUUUUAAGAAAUUAUAAUUGCCAUCCUUAUGGGUAUGAAGUGGUAUCUCACUGUGGUUUUGAUUUGCGUUUCCCAGAUUACUAAUGAUUUUAAGCAUCUUUUCAUGUGCUUGUUGGCCAUGUGUGUAUCUGCUUUAGAGAAAUGUCUAUUCAAGUUCUUUGCCCUUUUAAAAAACUACAUUGUUGGUGUUUUUGUAUUGAGUUGUGUUUUUAUAUACUCCAGAUACUAGACUGUUCAUUAUCAAAUAUAUAAUGUGCAAAUGUUUUCUUCCAUUAUGUGGAUUUUUUUUUUCAAUUUUUUGAUAAUGUCCUUUGAUAGAUAAAUGUUUUGAAUUUUGAUGAAGUCCAUUUUAUUUAUUUGACCCAUGCUUUUGGUGUCAUAUCAAGAAUCCAUUUCCAAAUCCCAGGCCAUGAAGAUUAACCCUAUGUUUUCUUCCAAGAGUUUUAUAAUUUUACUCCUUAUAUUUAGGUCACUGAUUCAUUUUGUGUUAAUUGUUGUAUAUGGUAUAAAUUCCAACUUCAUUGUCUUGCAUGUGAAUAGUUGUCCCGGCACCACUUGUUGAAGACACUGUUCUUUUGCCAUUGAAUGGUCUUUGGCAUCUUUAAAAUCAAUUGGCUAUAGAUGUAUCAGUUUAUUUUUGGAUGCUCAAUUCUACUCCUUUGGUCUAUAUAUCUAUCACUAUGCCAGUGCCAUGUUGUUUUGAUUACUGUAGCUUUGUGGUAAGGUUUUGAAAUUGGGAAAUGUGAGUUCUCCAGCUUUGUUCUUCUUUUUAAAAAUUGUUUGGCCUGUUUAGGGCCCCUUGCAAUUCCAUAUGAAUUUGAGAAUCAGCUUUUCCAUUUCUGCAUAAAAGGCCAUAGAAAUUUUGAUAGGUAAUAUAUUGAAUCUGUAGAUUGCUUUGGGUAGUAUUGCCAUCUUAAUAAUGUUAAGUCUUUGAGUACCUGGAUGUGUGUUUGAUAUCCUUCAGCAUUGUUUUUGUGUUUUAUAGUUUUCGGUGUACAAGUCUCUCACCUCCUUUGUUAUAUUUAUUCCUGGGUAUUGUAUUCAUUUGGAUACUAUUAUACAUGGAAGUUUUUCUUAAUUUAAUUUUUGGAUAGUUCAUUGCUGGUAUGUAGAAACACAAUGGAUUUUGUGUGUAACAUUUAUUGCCUUUAACAGUCAUUUACUUUCUUUUUUCCAUGUGCAAGCUGAAUCACGUGGGUAAAUAAGAAAGUGGAAAGUGGAACACUAAAGAACUUGAUCUGUGAUUUUACAACGAGAUGCUGCUCUCCAUAGGGAUGCUCAUGCUGUCAGCCACACAAGUCUACACCAUCUUGACUGUCCAGCUCUUUGCAUUCUUAAACCUACUGCCUGUAGAAGCAGACAUUUUAGCAUAUAACUUUGAAAAUGCAUCUCAGACAUUUGAUGACCUCCCUGCAAGAUUUGGUUAUAGACUUCCAGCUGAAGGUUUAAAGGGUUUUUUGAUUAACUCAAAACCAGAGAAUGCCUGUGAACCCAUAGUGCCUCCACCAGUAAAAGACAAUUCAUCUGGCACUUUCAUCGUGUUAAUUAGAAGACUUGAUUGUAAUUUUGAUAUAAAGGUUUUAAAUGCACAGAGAGCAGGAUACAAGGCAGCCAUAGUUCACAAUGUUGAUUCUGAUGACCUCAUUAGCAUGGGAUCCAACGACAUUGAGGUACUAAAGAAAAUUGACAUUCCAUCUGUCUUUAUUGGUGAAUCAUCAGCUAAUUCUCUGAAAGAUGAAUUCACAUAUGAAAAAGGGGGCCACCUUAUCUUAGUUCCAGAAUUUAGUCUUCCUUUGGAAUACUACCUAAUUCCCUUCCUUAUCAUAGUGGGCAUCUGUCUCAUCUUGAUAGUCAUUUUCAUGAUCACAAAAUUUGUCCAGGAUAGACAUAGAGCUAGAAGAAACAGACUUCGUAAAGAUCAACUUAAGAAACUUCCUGUACAUAAAUUCAAGAAAGGAGAUGAGUAUGAUGUAUGUGCCAUUUGUUUGGAUGAGUAUGAAGAUGGAGACAAACUCAGAAUCCUUCCCUGUUCCCAUGCUUAUCACUGCAAGUGUGUAGACCCUUGGCUAACUAAAACCAAAAAAACCUGUCCAGUGUGCAAGCAAAAAGUUGUUCCUUCUCAAGGCGAUUCAGACUCUGACACAGACAGUAGUCAAGAAGAAAAUGAAGUGACAGAACAUACCCCUUUACUGAGACCUUUAGCUUCUGUCAGUGCCCAGUCAUUUGGGGCUUUAUCGGAAUCCCGCUCACAUCAGAACAUGACAGAAUCUUCAGACUAUGAGGAAGACGACAAUGAAGAUACUGACAGUAGUGAUGCAGAAAAUGAAAUUAAUGAACAUGAUGUCGUGGUCCAGUUGCAGCCUAAUGGUGAACGGGAUUACAACAUAGCAAAUACUGUUUGACUUUCAGAAGAUGAUUGGUUUAUUUCCCUUUAAAAUGAUUAGGUAUAUACUGUAAUUUGAUUUUUUGCUCCCUUCAAAGAUUUCUGUAGAAAUAACUUAUUUUUUAGUAUUCUACAGUUUAAUCAAAUUACUGAAACAGGACUUUUGAUCUGGUAUUUAUCUGCCAAGAAUAUACUUCAUUCACUAAUAAUAGACUGGUGCUGUAACUCAAGCAUCAAUUCAGCUCUUCUUUUGGAAUGAAAGUAUAGCCAAAACAUAAAAAAAAAAAAAUCCUCAGUAUAGCUUGCAAUUAAGACCUAGAUCACAGUAUUUAAGUGUUUUGCGUUUUAUACAUGAGGUCAGUGCUACAGCCACCUAGCAUGAACUAACCCAGCUUCCACCUCCAUAAAGUUACCUAGAGUUGUUGAGUUGGAAUAUGUUCUGGCAUUUACCUGACCUGCCAAUCAUUAGGGAGAGGCAACAAGGUAAUUCAGCCUUUCCUCCUAUCAGCACAAAGAAACUCAAAGCUGUUUUUUCCCUUUCUGUUCCAAAGCAGUCUUAUCCUGACAGGAGCGGUCUAUACUAGUGCAGAUUUCAACACUUUUUUUUAACGUUUUAAUUACUAUAGUGUUAUGUAGAGAUUUGAUUGAGCAGCUAAUGUUUCUGAACUUUACUUACUAAUUUUCAGUGUCCUUAAGGGUUCUGUAGUGUUAUCAAAGCAAAAAGAAAAUGCUGCAUAAAAAUACCAAACUUCAGCAACUGUUAAUACUCAGAUCAUAUACCUCUUAAUAAAUAGCAUCUUAUGCUAAUUAGCCCUGCUAAACUAUGUACAGAGGAAACUGUUCAAGUAUUGGAUUUGAAAGUAAGUGACUUAUGUUUAACAGAACUAAUGAUGUAUUGAAACACUGUAUUAUGAAAAGCUAAAUUAUACAUCAUUGUAACUAUGUAGAAAGUGUAGACUAAUGUAUAAUCAAAAUGCUAAGGAUUUUUAUAUGGCCUUGUAUGAGGGGAGUUUGAAUGUUAAUAAACAUGUUUUCCACUUUAAGAUCCAGUAAA